ACUUCCGCUGGUGGCCUAGAGCGGGGCCCGGUAUGGAGGUGGGCUAGAGGCCGACGCCAGCCAGAGAGCGGUGAGGGUAGCGGCGGGCUGGAGGCCGUAGGUCGGGCGGGCGUGAGCGCAGGCGCGGCUUGUGCUUGCAGGGCCGCUUCGGGGAACCAUCGCGGCGCCUAGGUCCCGGUGGGCGGAUGGGGGAAGAGUCGGCGCGGGCUCGGCCGCUUCCCUCGGUGCGGGGGCGGGAGCACCCCUCGACGGCUGGCGGCCGCCUGUUGCCUUCCUGCGCGCUGGACCCGGCCGCUGCGACCCCCUGUCCUUCCGUUGUCUACACUGCGGUCUCGUGUGAGCUGUUUUUGAAAUGUUCUUUUGGGGCCAGAGUCUGGGCAUAUAUGAAUGCAAAUCCGUGUUUGUUCACAACUAAGCCCAGCUGAGACGAUCACUUUUCUGUAGGCCAUUUGUCCAGGUACAGAAUGAGCACAUGUUGUUGGUGUACGCCAGGUGGUGCUUCCACCAUUGACUUCCUAAAGCGCUAUGCUUCCAACACUCCGUCCGGUGAAUUUCAAACAGCCGACGAAGACCUCUGCUACUGCUUGGAGUGUGUGGCUGAGUACCACAAAGCAAGAGAUGAAUUGCCAUUCUUGCAUGAGGUUUUAUGGGAAUUAGAAACCUUACGUCUCAUAAAUCACUUUGAAAAAUCCAUGAAGGCAGAAAUUGGAGAUGAUGAUGAGUUAUAUAUAGUAGACAAUAAUGGAGAGAUGCCACUGUUUGACAUCACUGGGCAAGACUUUGAAAAUAAGCUUCGAGUUCCUCUUCUUGAAAUACUGAAAUAUCCUUACUUGCUUCUACAUGAACGUGUUAACGAGUUAUGUGUUGAAGCACUUUGUCGGAUGGAACAAGCCAAUUGCUCCUUUCAGGUGUUUGAUAAACAUCCAGGGAUCUAUUUGUUUUUAGUCCAUCCCAAUGAAAUGGUUCGGCGUUGGGCUAUCUUGACUGCAAGAAACUUGGGGAAAGUGGACAGAGAUGAUUAUUAUGACUUACAAGAAGUUUUACUUUGCCUUUUUAAAGUCAUUGAGUUGGGGCUUUUAGAGAGUCCAGACAUUUAUACUUCUUCUGUCCUAGAGAAGGGUAAACUGAUUCUUCUGCCCUCACACAUGUAUGAUACUACCAACUACAAAAGCUAUUGGUUAGGUAUUUGCAUGUUGCUGACCAUUCUUGAGGAACAAGCCAUGGAUUCCCUGUUGUUGGGCUCAGACAAACAAAAUGAUUUUAUGCAAUCGAUACUUCACACUAUGGAGAGGGAAGCAGAUGAUGAUAGUGUGGAUCCUUUCUGGCCAGCGUUACACUGUUUUAUGGUGAUUCUGGAUCGCCUUGGAUCUAAGGUCUGGGGUCAACUUAUGGAUCCUAUUGUGGCAUUUCAAACCAUUAUCAACAACGCAAGCUACAAUAGAGAGAUCCGACAUAUACGGAACAGCUCUGUAAGGACCAAGUUAGAACCGGAGUCCUAUUUGGAUGAUAUGGUGACUUGCAGCCAGAUCGUAUACAAUUAUAAUCCUGAAAAGACCAAAAAGGAUUCUGGAUGGAGAACAGCCAUUUGCCCAGAUUAUUGUCCUAACAUGUAUGAAGAAAUGGAAACAUUAGCCAGUGUACUUCAGUCAGAUAUUGGUCAAGACAUGCGUGUUCAUAACAGCACAUUUCUAUGGUUCAUCCCUUUUGUCCAGUCCCUCAUGGAUCUUAAGGAUUUGGGUGUGGCUUACAUAGCACAGGUUGUUAAUCAUCUGUACUCUGAAGUCAAAGAAGUCCUCAACCAAACAGAUGCUGUGUGUGACAAAGUCACUGAAUUUUUUCUUCUAAUUUUGGUAUCAGUGAUUGAACUGCAUAGAAAUAAAAAAUGUUUGCAUUUGCUGUGGGUAAGUUCCCAGCAAUGGGUGGAAGCCGUCGUCAAAUGUGCCAAGCUUCCUACCACUGCGUUUACACGGAGUUCUGAGAAAUCAUCUGGAAAUUGCUCCAAAGGAACAGCAAUGAUAUCUUCACUGUCAUUGCAUUCCAUGCCAUCUAACUCUGUACAACUUGCUUAUGUGCAGCUGAUUAGAAGUCUCCUUAAAGAAGGUUAUCAGCUUGGGCAGCAGUCUCUUUGCAAGCGAUUCUGGGAUAAGCUCAACUUAUUCCUUAGAGGAAAUUUAUCUCUAGGUUGGCAGUUGACUAGUCAGGAAACCCAUGAGCUACAAAGUUGCUUAAAGCAAAUUAUUAGAAACAUAAAAUUCAAAGCACCUCCAUGUAACACUUUUGUGGAUCUGACUUCUGCAUGUAAAAUCUCUCCUGCAUCUUAUAAUAAAGAAGAAAGUGAACAAAUGGGGAAGACGUCUAGAAAAGAUAUGCAUUGUUUGGAAGCUUCCAGCCCAACAUUUUCUAAAGAACCAAUGAAAGUGCAAGACAGUGUAUUGAUCAAAGCAGAUAACACUAUAGAAGGUGACAAUAAUGAGCAAAAUUAUAUAAAGGAUGUGAAACUAGAGGACCAUCUCUUAGCUGGGUCAUGCUUAAAGCAGAGUAGUAAAAACAUUUUUACUGAAAGAGCUGAAGAUCAAAUUAAAAUAAGUACAAGGAAGCAGAAGUCUGUAAAAGAGAUCUCUUCAUAUACACCAAAGGACUGUACUUCAAGAAAUGGUCCAGAAAGGGGAUGUGACAGAGGAAUAAUAGUAUCAACACGUUUGUUGACUGAUUCUAGCACUGAUGCUUUGGAAAAAGUGUCCACAUCGAAUGAAGAUUUCUCUUUAAAGGAUGAUGCUCUUGCUAAAACCUCAAAACGAAAAACUAAGGUACAGAAAGAUGAAAUCUGUGCAAAGUUAUCACAUGUAAUAAAGAAGCAACACAGGAAGAGUACUUUGGUCGAUAAUACUAUCAAUUUAGAUGAAAAUUUGACUGUAUCUAACAUUGAGAGUUUCUAUUCAAGGAAAGAUACAGGAGUUCAGAAAGGAGAUGGUUUCAUACACAAUCUUUCUUUAGACCCUAGUGGUGUUCUGGAUGAUAAGAAUGGAGAACAAAAAUCUCAAAACAAUGUAUUGCCAAAAGAGAAACAAUUAAAGAAUGAAGAAUUAGUUAUUUUCUCUUUCCAUGAAAACAAUUGUAAAAUACAGGAAUUUCAUGUUGAUGGUAAAGAAUUGAUCCCUUUUACAGAAAUGACCAAUGCUUCAGAGAAGAAAUCAUCUCCCUUUAAAGAUCUUAUGACUGUACCUGAAUCAAGAGAUGAGGAGAUGAGUAAUAGUACCAGUGUGAUUUAUUCUAACUUGACAAGAGAACAGGCCCCUGACAUCAGUCCUAAAUCUGACACCUUAACGGAUUCUCAGAUAGACAGAGACCUUCACAAAUUAUCUUUACUAGCUCAAGCCAGUGUUAUUACGUUCCCAUCCGAUUCACCUCAGAACUCAUCGCAGCUGCAAAGGAAAGUAAAAGAAGAUAAAAGAUGUUUCACAGCUAACCAAAAUAAUGUUGGAGAUACCUCCCGUGGACAGGUUAUUAUUAUUUCAGAUUCUGAUGAUGAUGAUGAUGAAAGAAUCCUGAGUCUUGAGAAACUCACUAAACAGGACAAAAUAUGCCUUGAGAGGGAACAUCCAGAGCAGCACGUUUCAACAGUUAAUAGUAAGGAGGAAAAGAAUCCAGUAAAGGAAGAAAAGACAGAGACUCUUUUUCAGUUUGAGGAAUCUGAUUCUCAGUGUUUUGAGUUUGAAAGUUCAUCUGAAGUGUUUUCAGUUUGGCAAGAUCAUCCAGACGAUAAUAAUUCAGUUCAAGAUGGUGAGAAAAAAUGUUUGGCUCCUAUAGCCAAUACUACAAAUGGUCAGGGUUGUACAGAUUAUGUAUCUGAAGUUGUUAAAAAAGGAGCAGAGGGCAUUGAAGAACACACAAGACCACGGAGUAUUUCUGUUGAAGAAUUUUGUGAAAUUGAAGUAAAAAAGCCUAAGAGAAAACGAUCUGAAAAACCAAUGGCUGAAGAUCCUGUGAGGCCUUCAUCUUCUGUCAGAAAUGAGGGCCAGUCUGAUACUAAUAAGAGAGAUCUUGUGGGAAAUGAUUUUAAAAGUAUUGAUAGAAGGACUUCAACUCCCAAUUCACGUAUUCAGAGAGCCACUACGGUUUCACAAAAGAAGUCUUCAAAGCUUUGUACUUGUACAGAACCCAUCAGGAAAGUUCCAGUUUCUAAGACCCCUAAGAAAACUCAUUCAGAUGCCAAAAAAGGACAGAAUAGAAGUUCAAAUUACCUAAGUUGUAGAACAACUCCUGCUAUAGUGCCGCCAAAGAAAUUUCGUCAGUGUCCUGAGCCAACUUCAACAGCUGAGAAACUUGGCCUGAAAAAGGGUCCUCGUAAGGCAUAUGAGUUGUCCCAGCGGUCUUUGGAUUAUGUAGCUCAAUUACGUGAUCAUGGCAAAACUGUUGGAGUAGUUGAUACCCGAAAAAAGACUAAAUUAAUUUCUCCUCAGAACCUGUCUGUCAGAAAUAAUAAGAAACUUCUGACUAGUCAAGAACUUCAGAUGCAAAGGCAGAUCAGACCCAAAUCACAAAAAAAUAGACGAAGACUUUCUGAUUGUGAAAGUACAGAUGUUAAAAGAGCAGGGUCACAUACAGCACAGAAUUCUGACAUAUUUGUACCAGAAUCUGAUAGGUCAGAUUAUAAUUGUACAGGAGGAACUGAGGUACUUGCCAACAGUAACAGAAAACAGUUAAUAAAAUGCAUGCCUUCUGAACCAGAAACCAUAAAAGCAAAACAUGGGUCUCCAGCAACUGAUGAUGCUUGCCCUUUGAACCAGUGUGAUUCUGUAGUGUUAAAUGGAACAGUACCAACAAAUGAAGUAAUUGUCUCCACUUCAGAAGACCCUCUGGGUGGAGGUGAUCCAACAGCACGUCAUAUAGAGAUGGCAGCUUUGAAAGAAGGAGAGCCUGACUCCAGCAGUGAUGCAGAGGAAGAUAACUUAUUUUUAACCCAAAAUGAUCCUGAAGAUAUGGAUUUAUGUUCACAAAUGGAGAAUGACAAUUAUAAACUCAUUGAACUAAUUCAUGGAAAAGAUACAGUUGAGGUUGAAGAAGAUUCUGUAAGUCGGCCUCAGUUGGAAUCUUUGAGUGGCACAAAGUGUAAGUACAAAGAUUGUCUUGAAACCACAAAAAACCAGGGUGAAUACUGCCCAAAACACUCUGAAGUGAAAGCAGCAGAUGAAGAUGUAUUUCGUAAACCUGGCUUGCCUCCUCCUGCAUCUAAACCUUUGAGACCUACCACUAAGAUUUUUAGCUCAAAGAGUACUUCACGAAUUGCUGGUCUUUCUAAAUCUUUGGAAACUUCUUCAGCACUUUCACCGUCUCUAAAAAAUAAGUCAAAGGGGAUACAGUCGAUUUUGAAAGUACCACAGCCAGUUCCCCUCAUAGCUCAGAAGCCAGUUGGUGAAAUGAAGAAUUCGUGCAAUGUUCUUCAUCCUCAGUCUCCGAAUAAUUCCAACAGGCAAGGUUGCAAAGUUCCAUUUGGUGAAAGCAAAUAUUUUCCAUCUUCCUCUCCAGUAAACAUUCUUUUGUCAUCACAGUCUGUCUCUGACACCUUCGUUAAAGAGGUCUUAAAAUGGAAAUAUGAAAUGUUUUUGAACUUUGGUCAGUGUGGGCCCCCUGCAAGUCUUUGUCAGUCCAUCUCAAGACCUGUGCCUGUCAGAUUUCACAAUUAUGGAGAUUAUUUUAAUGUUUUUUUCCCUUUGAUGGUAUUGAAUACUUUUGAAACAGUGGCACAAGAAUGGCUCAACUCUCCAAAUAGAGAGAAUUUCUAUCAGUUGCAAGUACGAAAAUUUCCUGCCGAUUAUAUAAAAUACUGGGAGUUUGCAGUUUAUCUGGAAGAAUGUGAACUGGCUAAACAGCUUUAUCCAAAGGAAAACGAUUUGGUGUUUUUAGCUCCUGAGAGAAUAAAUGAAGAGAAGAAAGAUACAGAGAGAAAUGACAUACAAGAUCUCCACGAAUAUCAUUCUGGUUAUGUUCAUAAAUUUCGCCGCACGUCAGUCAUGCGUAAUGGGAAAACUGAGUGUUACCUUUCCAUCCAGACUCAAGAGAACUUUCCGGCCAAUUUAAACGAACUUGUGAAUUGUAUUGUAAUCAGUUCUCUGGUAACUACACAAAGGAAGUUGAAAGCCAUGUCUCUGUUGGGUAGUCGGAACCAACUGGCUAGAGCUGUUCUGAAUCCAAACCCUAUGGACUUCUGUACAAAAGAUUUACUGACUACAACAUCUGAGAGAAUUAUUGCGUACUUAAGAGAUUUCAAUGAAGAUCAAAAGAAAGCAAUAGAAACUGCAUAUGCUAUGGUGAAACACUCACCAUCAGUUGCCAAAAUCUGCUUGAUUCAUGGACCACCUGGAACAGGAAAAUCAAAAACUAUUGUUGGCCUCCUCUAUCGUCUACUGACAGAGAACCAGAGGAAGGGGCAUUCAGACGAAAACUCCAAUGCCAAAAUCAAACAAAACCGUGUCCUCGUGUGUGCACCUUCCAAUGCAGCUGUUGAUGAACUCAUGAAAAAAAUUAUCCUUGAAUUCAAAGAAAAAUGUAAAGACAAGAAGAAUCCUUUAGGAAACUGUGGAGAUAUAAAUUUAGUACGACUGGGUCCAGAAAAGUCUAUUAAUAGUGAGGUUCUAAAGUUCAGUUUGGACAGCCAAGUAAACCACAGAAUGAAAAAAGAGUUACCUUCUCAUGUUCAGGCGAUGCAUAAAAGAAAGGAAUUUCUAGAUUAUCAGCUGGAUGAGCUUUCCCGGCAGCGAGCUCUAUGCCGAGGUGGACGGGAAAUACAGAGGCAAGAAUUAGAUGAAAACAUUUCCAAAGUUUCUAAGGAAAGGCAGGAACUUGCUUCUAAAAUUAAAGAGGUUCAAGGACGCCCACAGAAAACACAGAGUAUCAUCAUCUUAGAGUCCCAUAUCAUCUGCUGCACGUUGAGCACAAGUGGUGGUUUACUACUUGAGUCUGCUUUCCGUGGGCAAGGGGGUGUCCCCUUCAGCUGUGUCAUUGUUGAUGAGGCUGGACAGUCUUGUGAAAUUGAGACUCUUACUCCACUCAUCCAUCGCUGCAAUAAGCUCAUCCUAGUAGGAGAUCCUAAGCAGCUCCCUCCGACAGUCAUCUCUAUGAAAGCACAGGAGUAUGGCUACGACCAGUCAAUGAUGGCUCGCUUCUGCAGACUGCUGGAAGAGAAUGUAGAACACAACAUGAUCAGCAGGCUGCCCAUUCUACAGCUCACUGUUCAGUACAGGAUGCAUCCAGACAUAUGCCUCUUCCCUUCUAAUUAUGUUUAUAACAGAAACUUAAAAACAAAUAGACAGACAGAAGCCAUUCGAUGUUCAUCAGAUUGGCCAUUUCAGCCAUACCUUGUGUUUGAUGUUGGAGAUGGUUCAGAAAGACGGGAUAAUGACUCAUAUAUAAAUGUUCAAGAAAUAAAACUGGUGAUGGAAAUAAUUAAGCUUAUUAAAGACAAAAGAAAGGAUGUUAGUUUUCGAAACAUUGGCAUAAUAACUCAUUACAAGGCCCAGAAGACGAUGAUUCAGAAGGAUUUGGACAAAGAGUUCGAUAGAAAAGGACCAGCAGAAGUAGACACUGUGGAUGCAUUCCAGGGUCGGCAGAAGGAUUGUGUUAUUGUUACGUGUGUCAGAGCAAAUAGCAUCCAAGGUUCAAUUGGAUUCCUGGCAAGUUUGCAGAGAUUGAAUGUCACCAUCACACGAGCCAAGUACAGCCUCUUCAUCCUCGGACAUUUGAGGACCCUGAUGCAACUUCUUCCUAGGAGCUUUUGUGUACACGUGAACCAUUCGCCUUUUUUCAGCCCAGAACCCAAGUAUCUACACUGGGCUCUCAAGGAAAACCAGCAUUGGAAUCAGCUGAUUCAGGAUGCUCAGAAGCGUGGUGCCAUUAUUAAGACCUGUGACAAAAACUAUAGACAUGAUGCAGUGAAGAUUCUGAAACUCAAGCCUGUGCUGCAGAGAAGUCUCACUCACCCUCCUACCAUAGCCCCAGAGGGGUCCAGACCCCAGGGUGGUUUGCCCAGCAGCAAGCUAGACAGUGGAUUUGCCAAGACAUCUGUUGCUGCUUCUCUAUACCACACACCCUCUGACUCCAAGGAAAUUACUCUUACUGUUACUUCAAAGGACCCUGAAAGACCUCCUGUUCAUGACCAACUUCAGGACCCACGACUGCUGAAGAGGAUGGGCAUUGAGGUCAAAGGAGGAAUAUUCCUUUGGGAUCCACAACCCUCGAGCCCCCAGCAUCCUGGAGCAACACCUCCUACGGGCGAGCCGGGCUUCCCUGUCGUUCACCAGGACCUGAGCCAUAUACAGCAGCCCGCUGCUGUAGUGGCUGCUCUGAGCAGCCACAAACCUCCCGUGCGGGGCGAACCUCCAGCUGCCAGUCCCGAGGCUUCCACGUGUCAGAGCAAAUGUGAUGACCCGGAAGAGGAGCUCUGUCACAGGAGAGAGGCCAGGGCUUUCAGUGAAGGGGAGCAGGAGAAGUGUGGUUCCGAGACCCAUCACACCAGGAGGAACUCUAGGUGGGACAAGAGGACACUGGAGCAGGAGGACAGCAGUUCCAAGAAAAGAAAGCUUUUAUAGGAAAGCCCAGUGACAUGGGCCAGCAGCCACAGCAUAUUGUAAACUGAAGAUGACCAGCUCGUGGGACCAUCUAGAUAAGCUUGUUUUUUGUAAGGAGUUUGUGUGCUGUUGGAAAACAUGGAAAAUGCAUCCUUAACACCUGAGCCUCUGGUCAUCUUCAGUAUUUUCUGUCAUUUGCAAAAGCUUUCAGAGGGCAUUGUGUAUCCGUAAUAAUGUCCUUGAAGUCAGAGACUGGAAAUGUUGAUCUCUUAGUCUUCUAUAGACAAGGAGGUCAGACUGGAGUGAAUGUUGUAAAAGUUGAAAUGUAUAUUUGUAUAGCAAAUAACAAAAUCCUUUUAAAAUUUAAUCUAGUAGACCGCUUUUCUUUCCCCCUGUUUAAAAUGUUAAUCAGUUUUCAACAGAACAAACUUUAUAUUACCAAAAAAAAAAAGAUGGGAGGAGGGCGGGUCCUUUCAACCAUUGUUAGAGCAAGACAGAUAAUUAUUUAACAGCCUAGCUUGGAAUAAGCUGAGUUAGUGCUGGUGGGUCAGGUGUCUCUGGCUCUAUUAAAAAAAGCAAAAACCCCCCCAAAAACCUGGAGUCUCCUAGGGGACACUUUGGGCAGCACGGUUAUGUUAGGUAAAGUCUUGCUGACAUGGUGCAUUUUUAGAUAGAGUGCAUUGGCCCAGGGUAUUAUAUUUCUGUGAUGAGUUCAUUUACCUGUUUCAGUAUGCACAUAGUUCCCUAGCUAAAAUUCCUAAUCUUCUUGAGAGAGAAGAAUAUGGAGUGAAAGAAUAAUUCUUGAGCUAUCAUUCAAAUGCUCCCAGCAUAUUGUGAGCCUUGUGUGACUGGUGAGGUACAGACAUUUGGUUGCCAAAUGCUAGAUUAGCGCUGGGUCAGCUGUGGAAGAAUCGCCUCAGCUUACAGAUUGUCAGACAGAUCUAACUAGUUUUCCAGAAAGCCUGGGAAGCUGUGUGUUCAACAUUUCCCAAGGGAUUCUGAUCACCAGGCAGCUUGGGAACCACUGGGGCAGGCCAAAUAGAAUAUUUUGGGCGGGAAAGAAGCACCCGAUUUAAAAUGAAGCGUAACCAGAGGAGUUCAGAACUGGGAAGAGAGUGGUAGACUUCCUGUGAUCUUCAGAAAUCAUCUACCUGGUAAAAAUACAUGCUGUUUAGAAUAUCUGAUAGGUGUUUCCAGCUACUAUUAGAGGUGAUAGUGCUUUUGUGGGGGAAAAAAUUGGUCAUGGUGAAUGGAGAUCGAGGAAGCUCGGGACAAGGGAGGGGUGGGCUGCCUGAUUUUGUCCAGUUUUCCAAAUAUCCACGCAGUGAACUGGAGUAUCCUAAACAUGAGAAUGUACAGUUGACAGUUGUAAAAACUAGGGAUCUGUAGUGAAUGCUGUGCAGCCCCAUAUCUCAUUUGGGGGUAGGAAAAUAGCUGAAGAUUCAUGUGCAUUAUUUGACAUUUCCUUUGUCAUCUGCUUUUUAAGCAAAAAAGGGUUUUGUGUUAGAAAUUCUACUUGAGCAGAUUAUAAAGAGCUUUAAAAAACAACUUUCGGUUGCCAAAAGUUUGAGCAUUUGAUUUCAUUACCUGUGUCUCCCUCACUGGUGUCCAGACGGUCAACUGAAUACUCCUGAAACCCAGGGAGCAGGUGACUUCCUGGAGUGCUUUGUCCCCAGAGUCAGCCACUGCUUCCUCUGUGGGGGUGGAGAGUUUGUCUUUGGCCAUGCAGUGUGCGACAGUUCAGGACGGGUAGGGAUGGGUCCCAUUCUGUCUGGGUCAAGGGCUCUAUCAGCUUCUUCCAUGUGCCUUUGGGAAGAAAUCUCGUUACUUUAAGUUUGCUUUCCUGUUAUCUUGAUGAAGUGCCCAUUUUAGCAGACACUUGUAGUGCUGACCACUUAGGGAAUGUACAAACUCCUAAGCUUCUAAAGGGAGGCAUGGCAAAAACGUUGGGGUCAGGAUGUCUCUCACGCUGCUCAUGUUAAUACUAUUAACACAUGAUUUGAGAAAUAAGUUUUCUCUAAAAUGCAUAUUUUGCCGCCACACACUGAACAAUAUUAUUUCCAGUGAAGUUUGAUGCCUGUUCUUACGUUGUGUUCACCUGUUGGUUCACCACUCAGCAGAUCUGAUUCUGCAAGAAUUAAUGGUAGAACUAGAUCAUCCUUUCUAACAGACGAGCCUGUGUCCUGUGACGGCCUUUCACAGCGGAAUGCAGUUGUACCUCACAUUACUUUUGAAACUUCACUCGUUCCAGUUGGUACAAGUAUUUGCCAAAGCCAUUUCCUAUGUUCACCGUGGCCCCUCCUGAUGUGGCUGUCAGCGCAGCGUUGUUGAACAGGGCUAUUCUUUUUACAAGGUGUGAAGUGUGGCUCUUCGCUUCGUCUUUGCCAUGGCAUUAAAAGAAAGUUCCCUGUCUUCUUUCAAUAUUAGUUAUUUCAAAUGAAUAUGUGCUACUUAAAAGCUUGUUUUGUUUCUUUGUAUAUAAUUUGCCUUGGAUUUAUUGUGCACAGUUUGUUGAGUUGUAUGUUUUUGUGAAUUAUCAGGAGUAAAUUUGACAAGUACAUGUGAAUAACCUCCUGUAAAUGAAUUUUAUAACAAAAAUGUACUGAACUAUUUUUUAAAGUUGUGCAGAUUAGCAAUUUUUUGCUAUAGCUUUGACUUUUCUAUGCUGUGAAUUAAUAGCUGCGAUUUGGCAAACAGCCCUGUUGUCUUUGUUAAACCCUAAAUUUUAAGAGGAAAUGGCAGAAUUAAAAGCAGAAACAAGAAGAUGGACAUGGAUUAGAGGUUAUGUAUUAUGAAGUAAACUACAAGGUACUAACAUCAUUUCGUCUGCCAUUUGGUUUGCUUUAUGCUGAAAUUACUUGGUGGGGAUUUGUGCAAUUCAGAUAUAAAAAGUUUCAUUAUCCA